ACGGCCGUUUGCAGCCUCCGUGCCAGGGCCGGGGGUGCGGUUCGGGACGCGGGAUCCUAGGUCGGGUCCUGCCCCGCCCAUGUGGCGCCGGCGUCUGUGUUGUCUGCGGUCUCCAGGGCAGCGCCGGGGCGGGCGGGGGCCCGGGCGGCGGCGGCGGCGGCGCGGGAGGAUGCGGGGCCCGUCCGGGUCGCGGCCGCGGAGGAGCGCCGGGCAGGUGACGGGCGGUGGCCUCCCGGAUCUGGGGUGGGCGGCGCGCCCGGGGAGGGAAACGGGAAGGGCUUACUGGGGAUGGGGACGGCAGGAAACCACCCAAGCAAGCUGGGGAGGAGCCGGCGCGGGAGCCUUCGGGACGGAGUGGGGAGCGACAAGGGGGCGAGGCCGCGACAAGGGGCUGGGGGGCCGCCAUGCGAGGCUUCGGCGCCCGGGCACCCAGAGCAGCCCUGUUCCCGGUCAAUUAGGACCGGUCCCGGGCACCAGGCCCGCCGACUUGUCACUUCCUGGACCUCCAAACGCCCCUUGUGACAGGCCUUGUUCCUCAGGAACAAGCAAAGGUAACGCUUUUGUGAACCACAACUUUAAAUAUCAGCCAGCUGCUCCUAUCAACACGAGUAUCCCCUGUUAAUUUUUUGCAUUUUUCAAGAUGAGUAAACGUAAACUAAUUCCCAAGCUCUCUAUUCAAUCUCCUGUCCUUCAUACCAACUUAAAUGUCCAGUCCACACACCCACCUUUGAAGAAAGAAGACUUACAUCGGAUUUCAAAAGACUCCUUGGAAUCUGAUUCAGAAAGCCUCACGCAAGAGAUUAUGUGCCAUUCUGAGUUUGAUGAUCGAAUCCGGGGCAACGGUAUGGAGCCCGACAGCUUAGACGAGGAGGAAAGCCCUCGAUGGGGAAGCCUGCACGAGAUGGAAGAGGAAGCAAGUGGAAAAGCAGCUCAGAUGGCUCGCGAGCAAAACCACCAUACCUGGGACCAGGGCGCCAAUAACAGGCAACAACCAAUAGAAGACAAAUAUUCAGACCUCCGCUAUGACCCGAACUGGAAGAGUAAGAAGGAGGAAGGGCAGCUGCUGUCUGUGGAAGCGUUGCCGGAGUCCACGGACAGCUCUUUAGAAAAUCUGCCUUUGGCUCCCCUCUACCCUUCCCAGGAGACGUCAAUGGAACUCUCCGGGGGAAAAGGCGAGCAGAAAGAGAGUCCACAGAGUGCAGCUUCUUUACUUGGUAGUGAAUUUUUAAGCCCAAACUAUGAGCAUGGUGCCCGUCGCAGCAAGCCGUUUUCAGAGCUGAGCGACAGUGACCUGGAGGAGAAGUCGAGCAGCCUUUCUCCGUACGUGAAGAGCUCAAGUUCACAUAACGAGGUUUUCCUGCCGGGAUCACGUGGCCCUCGGCGAAGGAAAUCCAAACAACAUUUUGUGGAAAAAAACAAGCUCACUUUGGGAUUACCCACCCCGAAAACGGACUCUUAUCUUCAACUUCACAAUAAAAAAAGAGGGGAAUCUCAUCCAGAACAGAUCUCCUACCCCGUCAGAGUAACAGACAAGACGUCUAUUCAGAAUGCCAAGGAAAUGGAAAAUGCUGCCAUCGAUCCUGAAGAUAAAUGGCAUCAAAGAGCACAACAGCUAAAGAAUUACCAGGAACACUGGUCUCAAUAUGAAAGUACAAAAUCAAGCAAUGUACCAAGAGGGCAACCUUCUGACAUGGUGAAUGACCAUCAACCUUCCAGAAGACCAGCCAAGCUCAAGAUUCGAAAGCAGUGUAAACACCAGAAUGGCCUGAAGUCUUCCACAACGGAAGAGGUGACUGCCAGUCAGGGGAACCAGAAUAACCCUCCCAGGCAGCAACAAAACCAAAAUAAGCCUCUUGAUACUUCAACAAAGCCUGAAUCGAUUGUGAUUAUGCAUGCCUCUAACAAUGAUGUACAAGCCUCAAGGGCACUUAGAAGCCACAAUCUCAAAGAAACCUCCAAUACAUUUGCUCCACCAAAACAGGCUUUUGACAAGGUCUUAUCUAAAAACUCUACUGGAUGUGACUCUGGGCUGAAUGUUAAUAAAGAAAGAGGACACAAAGACCAAGAAGAGAAAAGAUUUUCAUAUCAGCAGCUACACACCCUUUCUGACAUGGAUUUGAACAACCUUAAUGAACUUUCUAAGAGACACGUGCUCCUGAGCCAGAAAGGCUCUCAGUUUGUUUAUCACAUAAAUACUCAUGGAUCAACCAAAAAUAAGAAACAACUCAAACAGCCUUAUACAGAGACAAAAUACAGGAACUUAGAAAUGUUAUGGAAAUUCCAUUCUUCUUCUGACAGCCAGACGGUUAGAGCUUCUCCAGAUUCAUGGCUCACCCAGAUAAUGGAGCAGCAUCAGCAAGCCUUGGUGCAGCUGACCGACGUGCAGCCCAGUGAAGGGGCCUUAUCCAGCGUCACGCUUCCACCUAUACUGUCAAGGGUAGAAAGUGAAUCCCAACUCAGUUCAGAGAGAAGCCAAAGAAACCAAGUGAAAAUUAGCCGUAGCAAUUCUGAAGGCUAUCUGUUUCAACUGGAAAAGGGAAAAAAGCAUAAGAAAAGAAGCAGCAGUAAGAACACCAAGCUGAAAGGUUAUCAGAAAAGAGACGUGAAGCUUGGAGGCCUCGGACCUGACUUUGAGUCCAUCAGAGACAAAACGCAAAAAUUAAUACAGCAAAAGGAAUAUGCAAAACAAGUCAAGGAGUACAACAUGAAGACACUAUCCAUUCUAUCAAAACCACAAACAGAAAAAACUCAAAAGAAAUCUGCUAUCCCUCGGCAGAAGGCUUUGGAAUACGCUAAGACCAUCCCCAAACCCAAACCAUCAAAUCUGACUCAUCAAGCAUCAAAGGAACAAAAAAAUCCAACCUAUGCUGGGAAAGAAGAAAGUUUACCUGAAAUCUCACUGCUGGAAAUACUGCAGAACAGACACGAAAGGGAAAAACAGGCUGUGGCUGCUUUCAAAGUCCUUCACAUCGUAUAGACAACAUUUGAUAGGAAGGAGACCAAAAAUGGUCCAGGAAUGAACGUGGAGAAAAGAAACGCCAACCACCUUCUCUGCGUUGAGAGUAAUGGCCUAUUAUUAUCAUCUAUCUGCCGUCCAUGUUUGCUUUCUGCAGGAUUUAAAAUAUGAGGCCCAAUUGGAUUAUGGUGCCAUAUUUUACUUUCUAGGAAGAAAAUUUUUUAAAUUAUUUAUUUUCAAAUCAGUUAGAAUUGGAGCUGAAUAAUAACUAGAGAAUAAAGCUUUUGUUUUAUAUUGAUCUUUUGAUUUCUUCAUCUCUACCCCAUUCCUUAGCAUAAUGGAAACCUUAAAGUUACCCAGAAAUAAAUGUAGCUGUGUUUCUCUCUUACCUUCCUAGUAAGAAAAACAAGUAUAAACAUUUCAGUUUCUCCUAAAAUGAACUCAGUCAUCCAUAAAUUUUGUGAUAACAUUUCAAAAUAUUACUAAAAUCUCCAAGUUUGGCAAAGGGCUUAUAUAUAUUAAGUUGAGGCCGGGCACAGUGGCUCACGCCUGUAAUCCCAGCACUUUGGGAAGCUGAGGCAGUUGAAUAGCUUGAGGCCAGGAGUUUGAGACCAGCCUGGGCAACAUGGUGAAACCCCAUCUCUACUAAAAAUACAAAAAUUAGCUAGGCGUGGUGGCGCAUGUCUAUAGUUCCAGGUACUCAGGAGGCUGAGGCACAAGAAUUGCUUGAACCCGGGAGGCAGAGGUUACAGUGAGCCGAGAUUGUACCAUUGCACUCCAGCCUGGGCAACAAAGCAAGACUCUGUCUGAACAACAACAACAAAAGGUUCCUGCCCUGACAGAUUCUCUGGUCGGGGUCACAGGGAUGUUAAGACAGCUGGCUGCCUGGGUCUUCGCUGACCAUGCUGUCCUGGGUGGCACUUUCUGCCACUGCCACAGUGGCCCCCUCUCUGUAGAAUGCAGUUUUCUUAGGUCCAGGGGUAUUGCAGGCAACAAGGACCUUUCACACAGGGAAGCCACUCCUUGCCCCUCUACCACCUCUUCCUUCCUUUUCCUAUAGAGGAAAAGUUCGUUUUGGGCUGAUCCCUGAGGAAUUCUUCCAAUUUCUUUAUCCUGAAACCAGUGUAACAGGACCCUAUGUGCUCCAAACUGGGCUUAUCUUGUAUGCUUUAUCCAAAGAAAUAUACAUGAUUACCCCAGAGACCUUUUCUACUAUAUCAAUAGUAGGGUUACUUGUCUAUGUAAUUUAAAAAUAUGGUGCCUCUAUUGGAGAAUCUGCUUAUCAACUCAAUGAGCAAAACAUUGCCCAACUAGAAGAGGUGAAGCAGGCUUCCAUCAAACAAAUCCAGGAUGCAAUUGAUUUGGAGAAGUCGCAGCGCUCACUGGUUCAGAAGCGCCAUUACCUUUUUGAUGUGCAGAGGAAUAACAUUGCUAUGGCUGUGGAGGUUACUUACUGGGAAUGACUGCAUAGAGUGUAUAAGGAAGUAAAGAAUCGCCUGGACUAUCAUAUAUCUGUGCAGAACAUGAUGCGUUGAAAGGAACAAGAGCACAUGAUAAAUUGGGUGCAGAGCAUCUCUGCACAACAGGAAAAGGAGACAAUUGCCAAGUGCAUUUGGGACCUAAAGCUGUUGGCAAAGAAGACUCAUGCACAGCCAGUUAUGUAAAUGUAUCUAUCCCAAUUGAGAGAGCCAGAAACAGUUGACUGACUAAAUGGAAACUAGGCUAUGUGGCAAAAUCUUUCUGUAUUGCCCUCUACUGAAGUAGAUAGUUUAUAUCUCCUAAAAAUGAAACAUUUGUUCCCUAUACUGAGAGAACUCAAUCUAUUGGCCAAUCAGAUGUUUCCCAUCCUUCUUACUCAGCAUUUGAGUUGUUCCAUGAUCAUUUUUUUAUUGUUGUUUUUUUUGCUGUUGUUGUUGUUUUUAGACAGACUCUCGCUCUGUCACCCAGGCUGGAGUGCAGUGGCACAAUCUCGGUUCACUGCAACUCCGCCUCCUGGAUUCAAGCGAUUCUCCUGUCUCAGCCUCCCUUCAAGCAAUUCUCCUGUCUCAGCCUCCCGAGUAGCCGAGAUUGCAAGCGUGCACUACCACGCCCGGCUAAUUUUUAUACUUUUAGUAGAGGCAGGGUUUCGCCAUGUUGACCAGGCUGGUCUUGAACUCCUGAUCUCAGGUGAUCCGCCCACCUUGGCCUUCCAAAGUGCUGGGAUUACAGGCGUUAGCUACUACACCUGGCCCUAUGAUCACUUUUGAAUAAGCAGUUUGCCUUUGUUAAAUCUUGGUGCCUGACUAAAGAUUACCAGGUUAUAGUUUAAAUUUGUAAUUAAUUCUACCAUCUUGCAAUAAAGUGACAAUUGAAUGAAACACAAAUAAAUAAAGAAUAAAGUUGAAAAAAAAUGAAGGUACAUCUGGCUGUGCCUGCUCAGAUAGAACAAAUCCUAAUGUUGUUCUAACAGAGCAUCAAGACAUUAGUUAGAAACCCUCCAACAAGUCCAGAAACACCUAAUGCAGGCAACUCUGAGAGACACACUUUAUCAAAGCUCCUUACUCCAAGUACAUAAAUUUGCUGGCCAUUUUGCCAUCACAAAUAUCUUAAAAUAUUGUCAAAUGUGUGUUUUCACACACACAAAAAUAGAUAAGACAAAAGCAUUCCAUAGUUUACUACUGAAUACAAAUGUUAAUAAAUAUUUUUUAGUUUUUAAAUCUUUUUUAAUAUUGCAAGAAUUCCCAGUCUUAAAAUCAUUACUGGAGAGUUUAAUUUUCUACUUCCUUCCUUAUAUUAGAUGGACAUUACAUUUUUAGAUAGGCAUAUCCAGAAGUGGAUAAUUUGAACAUCAAUUUGGGGAAAAUCUGUUUAUCUAUACGUGUGGUGUAAGGACUAGCUUUGGAAAUGUACUCCUAUGUUGUAUACAUUUUACAUAUACCAAAAUGUAGCAUAAAAGAUGCCUGUAUGAAACCUUCUCUUAAAACUGAAAGCAGUUAGAAUUGAGAGUCUGCAAAGAUAACAAGUAUCUGAAGAUAAACAGAAAACUGGUGAAUCAUGUUUCAGUGGGAUUUGGAAAAUGUAAUAUAUGAGGCAUUAGACAGGAAAAUCACAGGCCAAAACUACUCCUAAAAUGUAUUUAUAAGAGAAGAGGCCCUUCUAGGUGCAUGAAGACAUUUCUAGAAAUAUGAGGUAGAAUGAAUAACCUUCAUUAAUUGUUUCCGAAAUGGCCUUAAAUUCGAACUUAAUUUGGAAGAGAAAAAGAAUGCAUAUAGAGACAUUCAUAUUUAAAGGGAUAGGGUAAAAUUUUUAAAUAUUCCAUUUGUAUUAUCUUAAAAUAGUUUAGAGCUUGGAAAGUUUGUCACAUUCAACUGCCAGUUUUUCAGAAGAUGAAAUGGAGGUGAAGAGAAAGGUUACAUGACUCGGAAGUCCAUCAGUCCUACUGAGAGUAAUGGGAGGGGAGCCAGGUCUGAAUCUCCCAUCUUUGAACACCAGGAAUAGUACUUUUUAUUUGUCUAUGGAAAGAGGUUGUCCUUGUUUCUCUGUGUGGAUGAGCAACAUAUAGUUGCUAUGAAUUUCUAUUUUGGACCUGAAUUUCCACCAAGUUCAAUUUUUAGAAAUAUGCAUUACUAUGUACCUAAUAGUUUUUUAGCAUGUACAAUCUGCCAACUUCCUUACAACAUUGAUAAAAGUAGAAUACACAUAUAAAGCAACUCAAACUUAGAAACUGACCAAUAAAAGAGACACUAUUUAUUUUCUUUUUUUUUUCCAGAACAUUUCAAAAACUUCCCAUACUGUUUUUCUGUUAGCUUAAGCGUUGUUAAAUCCUUCACUUUCACACCUACUGUCAAGAACCCAAAUUUGGCUGAAGCAGCUUAAGUGAUUCAGUUCAUGUCAAACAACAUUUCACAGGAUUCUUACCCCCAAGGCAACUCUUUACUAUCCAGUACAUAAGACUCUAGAACAUUAAAAUUCUUUAUAUAGUGCCAUGUGGCAUCUAAAAUAACUUUGGCUAGGAAAUAAAACAUAUUUGCAGAAAGUUUGGGGUUGAAAUCAAAGAAUGGAUCAAAGUGGCCCUUCAUUUGGCUCCACGUCAUCUCACAAUAGUGAAAUACAGCAGAAUGUCACUAAACUACCAUAAAACUAAGGGGAGAGAUUUUGCAAAAACAGGGAGUGACAGACACGUUUUUUGCUCCUGUUUUAAAGUAAAUUGUACUAAUGACAACAAUAGUGAUCUUUUAUAGGCCCAAGUUGGAUCAGUGAUCAAUUCAUAGCAUUUCUGUUUCAAAUAUUCAAAAGCAAAAAAUAAUCUGCCAAUUAGAAAACAAAAAACUUCAAACUUAAGUGAUGUAAUGAUGGAGCACCUGUAUUUGACUAGAUGUUAUAUACAUGCCAUUGAAAGACAUAGUACCUAAUCUGCCUAAUGUCUAUAAACUGGUGCAAAUAAAAGACAUUUAAACCA